UAAAACAGACGAUCAUAAAGAUUUGUUGGACAGAAAUCAGAAAGCAAAGUGGUACCCGUCCCAACAUCCUUAGAAUUUUUUAUUUUUGAGACGGAGUCUCGCUCUGUCACCCAGGCUGGAGUGCAGUGGUGCGGUCUCGGCUCACCGCAAGCUCCUCCUCCCGGGUUCACGCCAUUCUCCUGCCUCAGCCUCCCGAGUAGCUGGGGCUACAGGCGCCCGCCACCACGCCACCACGCUACCACGCUAAUUUUUUUGUAUUUUUUUUUUUUUUUUUUAGUAGAGACGGGGUUUCACCGUUUUAGCCAGGAUGGUCUCGAUCUCCUGACCUCGUGAGCCGCCUGCCUCGGCCUCCCGAAGUGCUGGGAUUACAGGCGUGAGCCACCGCACCCGGCCACAUCCCUAUAAUAUUCUUAAGAGGACUUGAUGCCACCCUCCCCAAAAAAACCUGAAAUAUUCCGAAAGGUUAAAAUUGAUAAAUUCAAUUGACAUUUUGAAAUCAGAAGAUUCUGCCCCCGAAAUAAACUUGUUUUACUUCAUUUUACUAUUUCAAGAAAUUGUUGCGAUGCAAUAGGUAGUAGAGGAGACUUUUCCAUUAAAAUUAACACCAGAUUUGCUUUUGGUGGAAAGAAAUCUGAGAUAGUUCUCAUUGACAGCAUCCGCAAGCUGUUUUCUCUGAUGUUUUGAACAGGCAACCAUUCUUACUCUUUAUCUUAAGGUAGUUGAUUCCCAAGGAUAGCAACAGGGAGGAAUGCGCAAGGAAUUUGGUAACUUCAUUUUUCUCUGGUGUAACCAUUAUUUGUGACUAUGUUGAAGUUAGAUUUCUUCCCUAAAAGUGGCCUUGCUUUCUUGUUGAUUCUUGGUUUAAAUAUUAUUGAGCUUAAAUAGUAGUUGAUGUUUUACUGAGAAGUGUGCUCUGUGAUGGUGAGAUGUUUGAACUGUAGGAGUGUGGGAGAAGUGGGAUCCUUAACAGAGGGAACACUAAUUAUUAUUUGCUUUCUGUCAUCUGGAAGGUAUUCCAAGCUAGACUAACAGGUUUAGUAUGAAAGAAAUGUAAGCUUCAUAUGAUUUUUAUUUUUAUUUUUAUUUUUGAGACGGAGUCUCACUCUCUUGCCCAGGCUGGAGUGCAGUGAUGCGGUCUCGGCUCACUGCAACAGCCACCUUCCAGGUUCAAGUGAUUCUCAUGCCUCAGCCUGCAGAAUAGCUGGGACUACAGGUGGGCACCACCAUGCCCGGCUACUUUUUUUACAUUUUUAAUAGAGACGGGGGUUUCACCAUGUUGGCCAGGCUGGUCUCGAACUCCUGAUCUCAAGUGAUCCACCUACCUCAGCCUCCCAAAGUGCUGGGAUUACAGGCGUGAGCGACUGCACGCAGCCCAUAUGAUUAACUUUUGUCCAUGGAUUCUUACCUACCUCUUUUGGGAACUGGGUCAGUUUAGGUUUCUAAGGUAGGAGAGCCAUCUAGUAGGAGCAGGUUAAACUAGAUUUCUGAGGUCAUCUACUUAUGGUCAUAACAUUUAGUGUUGUGUGUUAUUAAAAAGUCAUAGGAUGCCAUCUGAUCUGUAUACCAUCUAACCUGUACCCUGUAUUUCUUUUAUGCAGAGAAGGUAGGAAAUACAGGUAAAUGUUACCUGAGUGGUUGGGUUUAUGAGUGAAGCUGUUUUUGCAUAUGUUUUGGUGUUUUCCAUUUGUUACUGCUGUAGUCAGCAAAAGUGAUUUUAAACACUAGAACUGUCUUGAAUAAAACCAUGAUUAUGUAUCCCUUUUCCAGGAAAAAUCUUUUGGAAGGUGCCAGAUGGUGUAUGUAGCAUGCUUUUCAGUGUAUAUGUGUGAUUAAAAAAAAAAAAACUUAUGUGUGUAUUCACGUACACACACACACACACAGAUGAUAAGAGUAUCUCUGAAAUGUUGUUAUACAAGAAAACAUGGGCCCUUCUGAGAUGGGGUAUACUAGGUACAUCUAUUCUGAAAUAAAAAAUAAUUUUAUAUGAAGUUGAUCCUUGAACAGUGCAGAGAUUAGGGCCACUGACCCCUAUGAAGUCAGAAAUCCGAGUGGAAUACCAUGGGAUCCAUACAAAGUACCACUAAUGAUACUGGGAGUACUCCCAAGAAGCAGAGAAAAGUAAUGACAUUACAGAAAAAGUGAAAUGCUUGGUAUGUACUAUGGAUUGAGGUUUGCAGCUGUGAUUGCCUGCCAUUUCAAGAUAAAUAAAUUGAGUGUAAGGACCAUUGUGAAAAAAGAAAAGGAAAUUCAUGAAGCUGUUGCUGCAGCUAUGCCAGCAGGUGUGAAAACUUCGUACUUUUUGCAAAGUACCUUUUCAUGUUUUAUUGAAAAUUUAGCUUUUAUGUGGGGGCAGAAUUGCUAUGAGAAAGGCAUACAUAUAAACUAAUGCUAUUCAAAAACAAGUGAAGUCAUUGUAUAACAGCUUAAAGCAGAAGGAAGGAGAAGGAUCUAAAACUGGGUAAUUUAAUGCCAGCAAAGGAUAGUUUGAUAAUUUUAGGAAGAGAUCUGGCUUAAAAAAUGUCAAGAGAACCGGAGAAAAAGCCUCUGCUGACCAACAGGCAGAAGAUGAGUUCCCAAACACCAUUCAGAAAAUCAUUGAGGAGAAAGUAUUAAAUAUAUCUUCCUGAGUGGGUGUUUUUUUGUAAAAGCAAGUUUAUUAAGAAAGCAAAAGAAUAAAAGAAUGGCUACACCAUAGGCAGAGCAGCCCUGAACAAGCUUUUAAUGCUGAUGAAAGUGACCUGUUUUGGAAAAAAUGUCACAAAGGACAUUUAUUAGUAAGGAAGAGAAAUGAGCACCAGGAUUUAAGGCAGGAAGGUGUACGCAAAUUCUUCUAUUUUAUGGAUAUGCAGUUGGGUUCCUUGUCUAUGAAGUGUCUAACCCCCGAGCUUUGAAGGAAAAAGAUAAGUACCAGCUGCUAGUCUUGUGGUUGUAUAAGGAGGCCUGGACAACAAGAAUCAUUCUUUCUGGAUUAAUUUCAUUGAUGCUUUGUCCCUGAAGUCAGAAAGUACCUUGCCAGCAGGGAUUGCCUUUAAAAAUUCUUUUGAUACUGGACUAUGCCCCUGGCCACCCAGAACCCCAUGAGUUCAACAUCGAAGCUGUGGAAGUGGUCUACUUGUCCCCAGACAUAAUGUCUCUAAUUCAGCCUCUAAAUCCAGGGGUUCAUAAAGAACUUUAAGGCAUUACACAUGGUACUCUAUGGAAAGGAUUGUCAGUGCUGUGGAAGAGAACUCCAAUAGAGAGAACAUCAUGAAAGUUUGGAAGGAUUACACCAUUGAAGAUGCAGUCAUUGUUAUAGAAAAAGCCGUAAAAGCCAUCAGACUUGAAACAAUAAAUUACUAGUGGAGAAACUAUGCCCAGGUGUUGUGCGUGACCUCACAGGAUUUACACCAGAGCCAAUCAAGGAAAUCAUGAAAGAGAUUGUGGAUAUGACAAAAAAGGUCUUUCAGCAUAAGGAUCUUACAGAAAUUCAAGAGCCAGUAGACAUCACACCAGAGGAAUUAACAUAAUAUAACUUGAUAAAGAUGAGUGCUUUGGAACCAGUGCUAGACAGUGAGGAAGAAGACUUUGAAGAAACAGUGCCAGGGGCCAAAUGCAGUGGCUCAUGCCUGUAAUGCCAGCAUUUUGGGAGGCCAAGGUGGAUGGCUCACUUGAGCCCAGGAGUUCAAGCCUGGGUAACACGGUGAAACCCUGUCUCUACAAAAAAUACAAAAAAUUUAGCUGGAUGUGGAGGUACACGUCUGUAGUCCCAGCUACAUGGGGGGCUGAGGUGGGGAAGAUCAGUUGAGCCUGGGAUGCAGUGAGCCAUGAUGGCACCACUGCACUCCAGCUGGGAUGACAGAGUGAGACUCUAUCUCAAAAAAAAAAAAAAAAAAAAAGUGGUGCCAGAACACAAAUUGACAGUAGACAAUAUGGCAGAAGGUUUUCAAUUAUCAAGACUGCUUUUCACUUCUUUUAUCACAUGGACCCUUCUUUGAUACUGGCACUGAAUCUAAAGCAAAUGGUAGAAGAAAGAUCAGUACUAUAUAAAAAUGUUUUUAGAGAAAUGAAACGGCAAAAAGUCGGGCAGAAAUCAUGAUGUACUUCUAUAAAGUCGAGUGUGCCUGCCACUUCUGCAUCCCCUUCUACCUCUUUCACCCCUGCAAUUCCUCAGACAGCAAGACCAACCCCUCCUCUUCAGCCUACCCAGUGUGAAGACAAUGAAGAUGAAGACCUUUGUGAUAAUCCACUUCCACUUAAUAGUAUAUUCAUAUUUUAAUGAUCUUCUGGUCAUUUGUUGCUGGAGUUGUCACAUUCUACUGCUCACUAGGACCUGAUUCUCUCUUACCAAAUAUAUUCUUCACAAUAAAAUACAAACCCAAGCAGUUAGGACUUCAGGAAUUAUUUCCUCAAGGUCAUAGCUGUGCUGUUUGUGGUAAAGUGAAAUGUAAACGACAUAGGCCUUCUUUGCUACUUGAAAACUACCAGCCAUGGCUAGACCUGAAAAUUUCUUCCAAGGUUGAUGCAUCUCUCUCAGAGGUUCUUGAAUUAGUGUUGGAAAACUUUGUUUAUCCGUGGUACAGGGAUGUGACAGAUGAUGAAUCCUUUGUUGAUGAACUGAGAAUAACAUUACGUUUUUUUGCAUCUGUCUUAAUAAGAAGGAUUCACAAGGUGGAUAUUCCAUCUAUUAUAACCAAGAAACUAUUAAAAGCAGCAAUGAAGCAUAUAGAAGUGAUAGUUAAAGCCAGACAGAAAGUAAAAAAUACAGAGUUUUUACAGCAAGCUGCUUUAGAAGAAUAUGGUCCAGAGCUUCAUGUUGCUUUGAGAAGUCGAAGAGAUGAAUUGCACUAUUUAAGGAAACUUACUGAACUGCUUUUUCCUUAUAUUUUGCCUCCUAAAGCAACAGACUGCAGAUCUCUGACCUUACUUAUAAGAGAGAUUCUGUCUGGCUCUGUGUUCCUUCCUUCUUUGGAUUUCCUAGCUGAUCCAGAUACUGUGAAUCAUUUGCUUAUCAUCUUCAUAGAUGACAGUCCACCUGAAAAAGCAACUGAACCGGCUUCUCCUUUGGUUCCAUUCUUGCAGAAAUUUGCAGAACCUAGAAAUAAAAAGCCAUCUGUGCUGAAGUUAGAAUUGAAGCAAAUCAGAGAGCAACAAGAUCUUUUAUUUCGUUUUAUGAACUUUCUGAAACAAGAAGGCGCAGUGCACGUGUUGCAGUUUUGUUUGACUGUGGAGGAAUUUAAUGAUAGAAUUUUACGACCAGAAUUAUCAAAUGAUGAAAUGCUGUCUCUUCAUGAAGAAUUGCAGAAGAUUUAUAAAACAUACUGUUUGGAUGAAAGUAUUGACAAAAUUAGAUUUGAUCCCUUCAUUGUAGAAGAGAUUCAAAGAAUUGCUGAAGGCCCAUACAUAGAUGUUGUGAAACUUCAAACUAUGAGAUGUCUUUUUGAAGCAUAUGAACAUGUUCUUUCCCUUUUGGAGAAUGUAUUUACUCCUAUGUUCUGCCAUAGUGAUGAGUAUUUCAGACAACUUUUAAGAGGUGCAGAAUCACCAACACGCAAUUCAAAAUUGAACAGAGGUAGCCUAAGUUUGGAUGAUUUUCGGAACACACAGAAAAGGGGAGAAUCAUUUGGAAUCAGCAGAAUAGGUAGCAAAAUUAAAGGAGUAUUCAAAAGUACCACAAUGGAGGGAGCUAUGUUGCCUAAUUAUGGUGUAGCUGAAGGUGAAGAUGAUUUUAUUGAAGAAGGUAUUGUUGUAAUGGAAGAUGAUUCUCCAGUGGAGGCUGUGAGCACACCUAAUACUCCCCGAAACCUUGCUGCAUGGAAAAUUAGCAUUCCAUAUGUAGACUUUUUUGAGGAUCCCUCCUCUGAAAGGAAGGAGAAAAAAGAAAGAAUUCCUGUGUUUUGUAUUGAUGUUGAAAGAAAUGAUAGAAGAGCAGUUGGACACGAGCCUGAACAUUGGUCUGUCUAUAGAAGAUAUCUUGAAUUCUAUGUACUUGAAUCAAAACUAACAGAAUUUCAUGGUGCAUUUCCUGAUGCCCAGCUUCCUUCUAAGAGGAUCAUUGGCCCCAAAAAUUAUGAAUUCUUAAAGUCAAAGAGGGAAGAGUUCCAAGAAUAUCUACAGAAACUUCUGCAGCAUCCAGAACUGAGUAAUAGUCAACUUCUGGCAGACUUUCUUUCCCCUAAUGGUGGGGAAACACAAUUUCUUGAUAAGAUACUACCAGAUGUAAAUCUUGGGAAAAUUAUAAAAUCUGUUCCUGGAAAACUAAUGAAAGAGAAAGGUCAGCAUUUGGAACCUUUUAUCAUGAAUUUCAUUAAUUCUUGUGAGUCUCCAAAGCCUAAACCAAGUAGACCAGAACUGACCAUUCUCAGCCCUACUUCAGAAAACAACAAGAAGCUUUUCAAUGAUCUGUUUAAAAAUAAUGCAAACCGUGCUGAAAAUACAGAGAGAAAGCAAAAUCAGAAUUAUUUUAUGGAGGUGAUGACUGUAGAAGGAGUCUAUGAUUACCUGAUGUAUGUAGGACGGGUAGUUUUCCAGGUUCCUGACUGGCUUCAUCAUCUCUUAAUGGGAACUCGAAUCCUCUUUAAAAACACCCUGGAAAUGUAUACUGAUUACUAUCUUCAGUGUAAACUAGAACAGCUAUUUCAGGAGCACCGUUUGGUCUCACUCAUAACACUUCUCAGAGAUGCUAUAUUCUGUGAAAACACUGAACCUCGCUCUCUCCAAGAUAAGCAAAAAGGAGCAAAACAGACUUUUGAAGAAAUGAUGAAUUACAUUCCAGAUCUGUUAGUCAAGUGUAUUGGUGAAGAAACCAAGUAUGAAAGCAUCAGACUUCUGUUUGAUGGCUUACAGCAACCAGUACUCAACAAGCAGCUGACUUAUGUUUUAUUGGACAUUGUGAUACAGGAACUGUUUCCAGAGCUCAAUAAGGUACAAAAGGAAGUUACCUCUGUGACAUCUUGGAUGUAAACACUUGGAUUUGGUAUAGAAUAACCCAUUGAAAUUUCUGCUGUGCGAGGGUGGUAGAAAUUUACUUUUUUGGGUAUAUUCUUAUAUAUAUUAUGUACAUCGCUGUCUGAAAUUUUAGUUAUUUUUUGUUUUUAAUAAAGACUAACACAAACUUAAUGAUUAAAAGUGAUUGAGUCUCAUAGUCUUUCAUUUGCUAGCUGUGAUCCAAAUUUUAUUAGAACAUAAGUCACUUGUUAUUGCCAUUUUUAAAAGAGAAAAUUCAUAAUGAUGUUAUGGCAAACAGAUAAGACUGAUAAACUUCGUAUUGUAUAGCUUUGAAAAUAAUUAUGCCUAGUAUGGAGAAACAGGAAUAAGAUCUGAUUUUCUUAGAGUUAAUAUAUUUUAGUAGAUUGGUUUUCCUUUUUUUUAUUUUGUACAUAGUUAACUGUGUAUCUAUAAAUAAAGCAUCCUAUAUGAGUUUUUAAUAAUAAA